CUGUUCGCCGCCUCUCCCACCGGCCCGAUGAGCUGCAGCGGCUCCGGCGCGGACCCCGAGGCGGCGCCGGCCUCCGCCGCCUCGGCCCCGGGCCCCGCGCCCCCGGUCUCGGCUCCCGCCGCGCUGCCCUCCAGCACCGCCGCGGAGAACAAGGCCAGCCCCGCGGGGACAGCGGGGGGACCUGGGGCUGGAGCAGCUGCUGGGGGCACGGGACCCUUGGCGGCGCGGGCCGGGGAGCCAGCUGAGCGGCGUGGGGCGGCUCCGGUGUCGGCGGGUGGCGCGGCGCCCCCGGAGGGGGCCAUAUCUAACGGGGUUUACGUACUGCCGAGCGCGGCCAACGGAGACGUGAAGCCCGUGGUGUCCAGCACGCCUUUGGUGGACUUCUUGAUGCAGCUGGAAGAUUACACGCCUACGAUCCCAGAUGCAGUGACUGGUUACUACCUGAACCGUGCUGGCUUUGAGGCCUCAGACCCACGCAUAAUUCGGCUCAUCUCCUUAGCUGCCCAGAAAUUCAUCUCAGAUAUUGCCAAUGAUGCCCUACAGCACUGCAAAAUGAAGGGCACGGCCUCCGGCAGCUCCCGGAGCAAGAGCAAGGACCGCAAGUACACUCUAACCAUGGAGGACUUGACCCCUGCCCUCAGCGAGUAUGGCAUCAAUGUGAAGAAGCCGCACUACUUCACCUGAGCCACCCAACCUAAAUGUACUUAUCUGUCCCCAUGUCCCCACACCAGCCUGUUUUCAUAAUAAACUUUAUUGUGACAGGCGGGGCUGAUCCCUCCCAUGUUGGGAGACACCAUGUGGCAAGUGACAAAGCUCUGAGCCCGCCCCUCUUGGGGCCACAGUGGUAGGGAUGGGGGAAGGGGAUGGACCCCAUGGCUGGGGUAGUACCAUGACUGGAGGCGGGGGAGGCAACCAGAGGCCUGCUGCUUUGGGGAGGUGCAUUCCCCCAACCAUGUCCCGACACCUCUGGAGUUCAGGCAAGGACCUUCCAGUCCUACUUGUCCUGCAUCUUCUCAAGGAUAGGCACAAUCAUGUCAAAUUUGGGUCGCUUUGCAGGGUCUUCAUUCAUGCAGAUCUUCAUGAGCUUACACACAUGAGGGGAAAUACCUGGUGGGAUGGUAGGCCGAAGGCCUUCCAAUGCCACCUGCGAAUACAAGAAAAAAAGCAGCCUCACAAUUUGAGUCUGUCAUGUAGAGAGAAGCCACUGGCCCUUGGGACAGGAUUACUGUAUAUCCGAACAAAUAUGUGAGGAGCCAAGGCCCACUACAGUUAUUUUCACCAUCACCAACCACUCCCGCAACACAAAUGUAUGCUGUUGUGCUCUCACCUUCAUUCCAAUCUCCAUAUUGGAGAGGUCAGCAAAGGGUACCUCCCGUGUCACCAGUUCCCACAGAAGCACUGCAAAACUCCACAUGUCUGCUGAGCGUCUGUUUGUGUCUUCAGGCUUCUUCUGCAGAGCUGGAGAGAUAGGGCUUGUCUGUUCUGGCCCCCUUGCCUGUCCUGUCUCUGCCCCCUUCCACUACUUCUGAGGUGGUCCUUUUUUACCUCCCGACAUGAUGACUUCACUCACCUUCGGGGGCUACCCAGGCAGGUGCAUACAUGCGACCAGGACAUUGGAAAGAGAACUUGACAUCAGCCAUGCUAAUUCGGGCAGUCAUGUCCUCAUCAAUCUGAGGAAGAGAAAACAGAUAGAAGGAGGUAAGUCAUAGAUAGGCAAAGGGCUUUUGGGGCCUGGGCCAGGAGUGAGCUUGUGGCCUCACCAUUACACUACGGCUAUUGAGUGCAUGUCGUGGGAUGAGGGGCUCUAGUGUGUGUAGGAAGGCCAUGCCCCUUGCCAUGUCCAAAGCAAACUUCACAGCCUGGCUCUGGUCCACGACGAAAUCUGAGAGGAGGCAAAAGUCAAAUAGUUCAGAGAGGCUCCCUCUCUGCCAUUUCCUCCCCAAGGAAAUUCAACAUCCCUACUCACUGGUGCCUUCAUGUAGUACAUUGUAGAGGGAUCCAUACGGCAUCCAGUGUGUGAUGAGAGUAGGAUGAGGAGCAGGUGGAGACUGGCAGGCACCUAGCACUGGGAGCACAUUUGGAUGCGAGAAAAUCCUAGAAGAGGGAGGGAGUGGUUGAGACCCAGUACAAAAGAUCUCUUUCAGUGCUAUUCAGGGUUCCUUGGAACUAGCAGCUUCCAGGUUACGCCUUGCACUACCUGAGCCGGGGACACUCUUCAUUGAAGUCCCUGCUCUUCCUUGUACUCCAGUCUCGAACCUUCAGCACCUUCACGACAAUGUCAUUGCCCUGCCAGCGGCCCUUCCAUAGCUGCAGGACAGGUAGGGGUUAGGAGGCUUGAAAUGUUGCUGCCACUUCCUUGCCCACUAACUGGAGGAAAAACUUAAAACAGGUACAAAGCAAGUAAUUUAUGGGGGUUUAGUGAGGGAAGGGCAAGAAGGGCAGGGGUCACCUCUCCAGAGUGAUUCUCGUUGAGCUUCGUCAGGAAGUUAAGCUGUUUGAAGUCAAUGCCAGAGUGUUUGUUCAGGGUUCCAUUUCCUAAGAGUGUGGGCAGGUCAGGUACCCAGCUUCACCCUAACCCAGCCCCAAGAGGCCAGGAUUAUUUCCUUUUACAACCCUUCUUCCCACAGUGGUGACUCACGGGGCCGAGUGCGGGUGGUCCCCUUCCAGAAUGUGUCCUUGUAUGGAAUACGGUUGAGAUUCUGGCCCAUCUUCUCUGCCCGCUCUAGGGAAGAAAAACAACCUAAGCUGUGGUACAGAGGGAGAAGACAGGUGGGAAGGGACGAGAGGACACAAGCUAGGGGAUGGGGAGAUGGACCUCGGAGAAGCUCUCUCAGGGGUGCCUUGGCUUUGUCCACAGGCAUCUCUCCAUACUUGUUACAGAUGCUGACAAGGGCCCCAUUUGCCACCAGGUCCUGGAAUGAAAAGGCCAUUAUGAUGAGAGCCACUGCUACCUCGCUGGCAGUCACUGAACCAACCAUGAAUGCACAAAUGUAGAACUUAAUCCUGUAAGUGUCACACAGUAGUACUGACAGAAUGGGUUGAGGGUUCCAAAAUCUCCCACCAAGGCUCAGACUUUACUUCCUACCCAUCUCAGGAAUUAAGGGCUGAGUACUCACCUCUGCCACUUGAUCUUGGCCCCAAAAACAGGCAUAGUGCAGGGGCACAUUCCCGUGUUCAUUCACUGCAUUGAUGUCUGCCUUGUACUGCAAUAGCUGGACCCCAUGGCCAGACAAAAAGAAGAGGCAGAAAGUACAGUCAGUUCCAAAUGAGAUACUGGUGUCAGGGCAUGGGAAAAGGGGGAAGAGCACACAUGCUUUCUACUGUAUGUUACAGUGCCUGUGACUGACCCUCAUGGCAUGUAUGUGAUGUGGAUGACGAAGGAGUUUGUACGUACCUUCUGUACAAUAUCACGGUGUCCAUGACUGGCUGCCAGAUGCAGGGGGGUGUCAUCCCCACGGUUCAUUACAUUGAUCCGUGCCCCCCGCAUGAUCAACAUCUCAACCACAGCAGAGCGGCCCUCUCGGCAGGCCCAGUGCAAGGGGGAGAAGCCAUGAUCGUCCCUUUGAGGAAGGGGCAAUGGUCAUUGAGCUGGAGGUGGGAUGGGGCAAAGGUUUUGAUUCCUGAAAAACUGAUAAUUACAUACUCUCUGGGAAGGCUUACCUCUCUAGGACUUUGAUUCUCAUUCAUGCCAGCAACUCCCAAAGCUGUCCAUUUCAGACCUUCCCCUGAGCUUCAAACCAAACCAACCACCUAGAUAUCUCAACAACCUCUAUAAAAAAAUGUGUUAUCUUCACCAUAUCCCACAUCUCAUUUCCUUAGGUGGUAGUGCUCUUCCCCUGGUUUCUCUUGCACCCCUUCUGCAACAUCUAUUGGUCCUUUCUGUUUUCCACCACAUCUUAUAUGUCCCCCUACUUCAGCACUUGUUGCACUGGAUUGUAAAAAUCUGUUAAUGGACUGUCUUGUCUGUUAGACCUUUAAGUUUCUUGAGGGAAUGGAUUGACAGCAGCUGUUCAGUGCAUGUUAGUGGGGGAGAAGGGUGUCUUGGAGAAGGCAGGCCACAACUUAUAGAAGAGGGAACAAACUUACUAUUUGGCUCUGGUACUGAAACUAACAUCUAAAAAUGGAAUGGAAUUUAAAUGAUGUUUUGGAAGGGUUUAUGUUGAAAAGGAGAAAUGCUUUUGACUACUGAUGAGGUAGAUAACAAACCACCAUGCAAAGCAGGAUUCCCCUACUUAGCAAUCCUGUGCAUAGAAAACAGAAGAAAAUGAGAAUGGCUGUUUUGGGAUUAAAACUAUACCUGAUUUUUUUCUUUUCCAAGAAAUAUGUAUUUUAUAAAGUAAAGUAUACAAACAAAACAAAACAAUUGGUUUGGAGCUGGGCCUGCCUGACAGCCUGGGGCCAUAAAAGGAAAUUCCCUCCAGUUCGGGGCUGCAGAUUCAAGGGGCGGAGCAGGGGGCGGUCCGUGGUCUGGGCCAGCAGCCUCCGGAUGCCUUAGUGUUGUGGUCACUUCCUGUGUGCGACUCUAGGCAAGGCCUGGAGCUGAUCAGGGGUCUGGCCAUCCAGAUGCCCGUACAGCUGAAGGGGUUGGGGGGUGUGGCCUUUAAGUUAAUCAUUUUCCUCCACAACUUGCUCGCAUCUGCUAACACAGAAAUAGCCAAAAGCUUUUCCUUGAGAUGGGAUUAUCCCCAGGAAGCAUUACGCCCCCUGUUUAUCAGUUGGUCUUGCCUCCUAGACCUUUAAUUUGUGCCCUGACUUAUCAGCUUCCAGUACUGCCUGUGGCGCCAGGGCAGGCCAAACUCGGGGGGCAAAAGUAUGGGCACAAGGGUUCUGUUCACUAUCAGGCUGCCUGCCACCUCAGGGCCUGGACUUCUAUCUCAAGAAGACCUGCAAGGAAUUAACCCCCUCUUCAUAUCCAGCAUAUAGCCAACUUUGGCCCCCAUACUUUACUCCUCAAACCAGCACCACAACCUUCCAGUUUCAUUAAUUCCACCCCUUUUCCUUCUGGCAGCAUCUUCCUAGAGUCUUCCUAGACUCAGCUAGAGUCUUCCUAGAUGCUAGGCCCACUGGGCAACUGCCUAAGCCUCUAUUUCCUCACCAACAAAACAGUAACAGUGCUUACUGUCUUUAUCAGGGUACCCUUUGAGAAUUAUAUGAAAAAUGGAACAAAUGACUUUGCAAAGUAUUAAAGAGAAAUAGUGUAGAACCUAAUGGGAACCAGUGAAGUCUAGACUAAGAUGACAGGUGAUCCUGACCUGUCAAACCUAAAAACUAAACUCCACCAAUUUUAAAAAAUAAAGAAUUUGAUUUUGCCA